AGUGCUGGGAUUACAGGCUUGAGCCACCACGCCCGACCUCUCCCGAGGUUCUGAUGGCUUCUCCCGAUGUUUCCUUAUGUGGGAAUGGAAUCCACAGUAGUGGGUCCCUAAUUGCCUUCUGUGAGAAAAGACAGGAACAGGCUUCAGGAGGGGAGCUUCCUGCUGCAGGCAGCGUGUUCAGGGCCUCUGGAUCCACGAGGGCCGAUGCCCGGGGGGCCGGCUGUGUUACCUGGAGCACUUGCUCCGUGGAUCUCUUCGGUAGAACACGCGCUCAGCGGUAGCUGGAGCUCCAGCUCUUGGCAGCGCUCAGAUCCUAUGCCUGUACUGUAACCGUCGCCCCAGGUUCCUCCCGUGGCUGGGAAGCUGCAGUAAAGGCACGUUCAGGACUCAGGACCGUGGCUGCAGCAGUGGCCAGACGGCUGAGGGCGUGCGCUGCUCCUGGGCCAGACUUGUCUGCCCAGCCCCGAACCUUUUCCAGCACCGUGUUUGUUGAGAUUCUCCAGUCUUCCGAGGCUGCUGCUGAUGGUGACACUAAGCUGAAAACUGUACGGGGUGUCGUGACAAGGUACUGCAGCGAUUAUGGCAUGAUUGAUGAUAUGAUCUACUUCUCCAGUGAUGCUGUGACUAGCAGAGUGCUUCUGAAUGUUGGACAGGAAGUGAUUGCAGUUGUGGAAGAAAAUAAAGUGUCCAAUGGACUGAAAGCAAUCAGGGUAGAAGCUGUCUCUGAUAAGUGGGAAGACGACAGCAGAAACCAUGGGAGUCCCUCAGACUGCGGCCCCCGAGUGUUGAUUGGCUGUGUGACUUCCCUGGUGGAGGGCGCAGGCUGUAUCAGUCAGACCACCUACUUCUCUCUGGAGAGUGUGUGCGAAGGCUUCGAGCCCUGCAAGGGAGACUGGGUGGAGGCUGAGUACCGGAUCCGGCCUGGCACGUGGAGCAGCGAAGCCACCUCAGUGAAGCCACUGAGAUACAAGCGCGUGGACAAGGUCUGCAUCUCUAGCCUCUGUGGAAGGAACGGGGUGUUAGAGGAAAGCAUCUUCUUUACCUUGGACUCCUUGAAACUGCCAGAUGGGUACACACCCCGGAGAGGUGACGUGGUCAAUGCAGUGGUGGUGGAGAGCAGCCAGUCAUGCUAUGUCUGGAGGGCACUUUGUAUGACCCUAGUGAAGAGGCGAGACGCCGCCCCUGUUCAUGAGGCCACUCAUUUCUAUGGAACGAUUUUGCUGAAGAACAAAGGUGAUAUUGAAGUUACACAGGUGACGCAUUUUGGAACCCUAAAGGAAGGAAGAAGUAAAACCAUGGUGAUCUGGAUAGAGAAUAAAGGAGACAUUCCUCAAAACUUAGUCAGCUGUAAACUGGCUGGCUGGGAUAAAUCUAAACAAUUCAGAUUCCAAAUGCUGGAUAAAGACCAGAUGUGCCCCGUGGUAUCUUUUGUUUCUGUUCCUGAGAAGGAGAAUUCAUCAGAUGAAAAUAUUAAUUCAUUAAAUAGCCACACAAAAAACAAAACCUCUCAGAUGUCGGAGAGCAGUUUGGUGAACAACAGAGGAAUCUCUCCAGGUGAUUGUACCUGUAAAGGAGAAAAUGGAGAAAAAGACAACAUUCUAUCAAGGAAGCAGAUGACAGAGCCUGAGCCUGGGGGGCUUGUCCCUCCAGGGGGAAAAACCUUCAUUGUGGUCAUCUGUGACGGAAAAAAUCCUGGCCGCUGCAAGGAGCUCCUUUUGCUCUGUUUUUCCGAUUUCCUAAUUGGGCGAUACCUUGAAGUAAAUGUUAUCAGUGGGGAGGAGUCACUAAUUGCUGCGCGCGAACCAUUUUCUUGGAAAAAGCUUAAAAGUUCACAAGCGUUAACAUCCGCAAAAACUACAGUUGUUGUGACCGCACAGAAAAGGAACUCAAGACGACAACUUCCAAGUUUUCUUCCCCAAUAUCCAAUCCCAGAUAGACUUAGAAAAUGUGUGGAACAAAAAAUUGACAUCCUGACUUUCCAGCCAUUACUUGCAGAGCUUCUGAACAUGUCAAAUUACAAGGAGAAGUUUUCGACUUUGCUGUGGCUUGAGGAGAUUUAUGCAGAAAUGGAACUGAAAGAGUAUAACAUGAGCGGGAUCAUCUUAAGAAGGAAUGGGGAUCUGCUGGUUCUGGAGGUCCCAGGGUUGGCCGAAGGGAGGCCUUCUCUCUACGCAGGUGAUAAACUGAUUUUAAAAACUCAAGAGUACAAUGGACAUGCCAUCGAAUACAUCAGCUACGUGACUGAGAUUCAUGAAGAAGAUGUAACUCUUAAAAUUAAUCCAGAAUUUGAACAAGCCUAUAACUUUGAACCUAUGGAUGUGGAAUUUACAUAUAAUAGGACCACAAGCAGACGGUGUCACUUUGCACUUGAACACGUCAUCCACUUAGGUGUAAAAGUGUUGUUUCCAGAAGAAAUUAUUUUACAGUCUCCACAAGUGACGGGAAAUUGGAACCAUGCACAAGACACCAAAAGCAGUGGACAGUCCACCAGCAAAAAGAAUAGGAAAACAAUGACGGACCAAGCUGAGCAUGGAACAGAGGAGAGGCGUGUUGGUGACAAGGACCUGCCGGUGCUGGCACCCUUUACUGCAGAGAUGAGCGAUUGGGUAGAUGAAAUUCAGACCCCUAAAGCAAGAAAGAUGGAGUUUUUCAACCCAGUGCUAAAUGAAAAUCAGAAGUUAGCAGUUAAAAGGAUUCUGAGUGGUGACUGCCGUCCCCUCCCGUAUAUUCUCUUUGGACCUCCUGGUACUGGAAAGACAGUGACAAUAAUAGAGGCUGUUUUACAGGUACACUUUGCCUUGCCGGACAGUCGGAUUUUAGUCUGUGCGCCCUCCAACAGUGCUGCUGACCUCGUGUGUCUGCGGCUGCACGAGAGCAAGGUGCUACAGCCGGCCACCAUGGUCCGGGUGAACGCCACCUGCAGGUUCGAGGAGAUAGUUAUUGACGCCGUCAAACCGUAUUGCAGAGACGGAGAAGACAUCUGGAAAGCCUCACGCUUCCGGAUAAUCAUCACCACAUGCAGCAGCUCAGGGCUGUUUUACCAAAUAGGAGUGAGAGUUGGGCACUUCACUCACGUGUUUGUGGACGAGGCUGGGCAGGCAAGUGAGCCGGAAUGCCUCAUUCCUCUGGGGCUGAUGUCGGACAUCAGUGGCCAGAUCGUGCUGGCAGGAGACCCCAUGCAGCUCGGCCCAGUCAUUAAGUCCAGACUCGCCAUGGCCUAUGGGCUGAACGUGUCCUUUUUGGAACGGCUGAUGUCUCGACCCGCGUACCAGAGGGACGAAAAUGCUUUCGGUGCUUGUGGCGCACAUAAUCCCCUGUUGGUCACAAAGCUGGUGAAGAACUACCGGUCCCACGAGGCCCUGCUGAUGCUGCCCUCACGGCUGUUCUACCACAGGGAACUCGAGGUCUGUGCGGACCCCACAGUGGUGACCUCCUUGCUGGGCUGGGAGAAGUUGCCUAAGAAAGGCUUCCCUCUCAUCUUCCAUGGUGUGCGGGGCAGCGAGGCACGGGAGGGAAAAAGCCCAUCGUGGUUCAACCCGGCCGAGGCCGUCCAGGUCCUGCGCUACUGCUGCCUCCUGGCCCACAGCAUCUCCAGUCAGGUGUCUGCCAGCGACAUUGGCGUCAUCACGCCCUACCGGAAGCAGUGGCUCUGGAGCUCUGGUGGGGACACAGGUGCCUCCCAUGCCGAACACCAGGUUUCAUUCAUGAAGCAUGUGUCCCUGUGGUGUUCACACCACCAAGCAGAACUUGGAAAGAACCCCCAAAAUACAGAAGAAAAGGUGGAGAAAAUCAGAAUUCUUUUGCGUAAUGUUGAUCUGAUGGAUAUAAAGGUUGGAUCAGUAGAGGAGUUUCAAGGACAAGAGUAUCUGGUCAUCAUCAUUUCGACCGUACGGUCAAAUGAAGAUAGAUUUGAAGAUGAUCGAUAUUUUUUGGGUUUCUUGUCCAACUCAAAAAGAUUUAAUGUUGCAAUCACCAGACCCAAAGCUUUGCUGAUAGUGCUGGGAAACCCCCAUGUUCUCGUUCGAGACCCCUGUUUUGGUGCUUUGCUGGAAUACAGUAUUACAAACGGUGUUUACAUGGGAUGCGAUUUACCUCCUGCACUGCAGUCUCUGCAAAACUGUGGCGAGGGGGUGGCAGACCCCUCCUACCCAGUGGUGCCAGAAUCCACAGGACCAGAGAAGCAUCAGGAGCCCAGCUGAUCUGCAGUGGCUGACAGCAGGGAGGCCAUGUGCUCAGCCUGGCCACGUUGCCGUUACAGUCUGCUCCGUGGCUCCUGUGGCCUGCCCUUGUCUCGCAGCCAGGCAGGGUCGUGUGUGGGUGUGGGGCUGCCAGGUUGGACGCAGCUGCUGCUGCCCUGACUUUGGCAUAUGCCAGCCUGUUCCUGCCACAGGGCAGUCACUGCCGCCUACCCUGAAAUAAACCCUCGAGUGACCCCCA